AUGGAAGGCAACCAGACAUGGAUCACAGACAUCACCCUGCUGGGAUUCCAGGUUGGUCCAGCACUGGCGAUUCUCCUCUGUGGACUCUUCUCUGUCUUCUAUACACUCACCCUGCUGGGGAAUGGGGUCAUCUUUGGGAUUAUCUGCCUGGACUCUAAGCUUCACACACCCAUGUACUUCUUCCUCUCACACCUGGCCAUCAUUGACAUGUCCUAUGCUUCCAACAAUGUUCCCAAGAUGUUGGCAAACCUAAUGAACCAGAAAAGAACCAUCUCCUUUGUUCCAUGCAUAAUGCAGACUUUUUUGUAUUUGGCUUUUGCUGUUACAGAGUGCCUGAUUUUGGUGGUGAUGUCCUAUGAUAGGUAUGUGGCCAUCUGCCACCCUUUCCAGUACACUGUCAUCAUGAGCUGGAGAGUGUGCACGAUCCUGGUUCUCACGUCCUGGUCAUGUGGGUUUGCCCUGUCCCUGGUACAUGAAAUUCUCCUUCUAAGGUUGCCCUUCUGUGGGCCCCGGGAUGUGAACCACCUCUUCUGUGAAAUUCUGUCUGUCCUCAAGCUGGCCUGUGCUGACACCUGGGUUAACCAAGUGGUCAUAUUUGCUACCUGUGUGUUUGUCUUAGUCGGGCCUCUUUCCUUGAUUCUGGUCUCCUACAUGCACAUCCUCGGGGCCAUCCUGAAGAUCCAGACAAAGGAGGGCCGCAUAAAGGCCUUCUCCACCUGCUCCUCCCACCUGUGUGUGGUUGGACUAUUCUUUGGCAUAGCCAUGGUGGUUUACAUGGUCCCAGACUCUAAUCAACGAGAGGAGCAGGAGAAAAUGCUGUCCCUGUUUCACAGUGUCUUUAAUCCAAUGCUGAACCCCCUGAUCUACAGCCUGAGGAAUGCUCAGUUGAAGGGCGCCCUCCACAGAGCACUCCAGAGGAAGAGGUCCAUGAGAACGGUGUAUGGGCUUUGCCUUUAA